AUUCACCCUCCCACUUGGGGCUAAUGCACAGACAUGAACAUCUAUUGAGGAAAACCACAAAAAACUUCAAAACAGCUACAACGGUAUCCUAAGAAUAUUUCAAUUAAAUAUUAGUAUGUCUGCUGAAGGCACUUAAUUAUUAAGAAACUUAAAAUUAUCAAUCUUUCUUGAAUUUCUGAUAGAGAAGUAAAACUAUUUUCCAAAACUAUUUUUCAGAAUGUUCACUGAUACAUAAAAACUGCUAGCAUCUAAUUAAAGAUCACUAAGGGUUAAAUACUGUUCUCUGGCCCUUACUGCGCACACCCUGCCAAAACAUCCUCUAAGCUUUUAAAUAUUGCUUCGAUGGUCUGAAUUUUUAUUUCCAGGGAAAAAGAGAGUUUUGUCCCACAGUCAGCAGGCCACUAGUUUAUUAACUUCCAGUCACCUUGAUUUUUGCUAAAAUGAAGACUCUGCAGUCUACACUUCUCCUGUUACUGCUUGUGCCUCUGAUAAAGCCAGCACCACCAACCCAGCAGGACUCACGCAUUAUCUAUGAUUAUGGAACAGAUAAUUUUGAAGAAUCCAUAUUUAGCCAAGAUUAUGAGGAUAAAUACCUGGAUGGAAAAAAUAUUAAGGAAAAAGAAACUGUGAUAAUACCCAAUGAGAAAAGUCUUCAAUUACAAAAAGAUGAGGCAAUAACACCAUUACCUCCCAAGAAAGAAAAUGAUGAAAUGCCCACGUGUCUGCUGUGUGUUUGUUUAAGUGGCUCUGUAUACUGUGAAGAAGUUGACAUUGAUGCUGUACCACCCUUACCAAAGGAAUCAGCCUAUCUUUACGCACGAUUCAACAAAAUUAAAAAGCUGACUGCCAAAGAUUUUGCAGACAUACCUAACUUAAGAAGACUCGAUUUUACAGGAAAUUUGAUAGAAGAUAUAGAAGAUGGUACUUUUUCAAAACUUUCUCUGUUAGAAGAACUUUCACUUGCUGAAAAUCAACUACUAAAACUUCCAGUUCUUCCUCCCAAGCUCACUUUAUUUAAUGCAAAAUACAACAAAAUCAAGAGUAGGGGAAUCAAAGCAAAUGCAUUCAAAAAACUGAAUAACCUCACCUUCCUCUACUUGGACCAUAAUGCCCUGGAAUCCGUGCCUCUUAAUUUACCAGAAAGUCUACGUGUAAUUCAUCUUCAGUUCAACAACAUAGCUUCAAUUACAGAUGACACAUUCUGCAAGGCUAAUGACACCAGUUACAUCCGGGACCGCAUUGAAGAGAUACGCCUGGAGGGCAAUCCAAUCGUCCUGGGAAAGCAUCCAAACAGUUUUAUUUGCUUAAAAAGAUUACCGAUAGGGUCAUACUUUUAACCUCUAUUGGUACAACAUAUAAAUGAAAGUACACCUACACUAAUAGUCUGUCUCAACAAUGAGUAAAGGAACUUAAGUAUUGGUUUAAUAUUAACCUUGUAUCUCAUUUUGAAGGAAUUUAAUAUUUUAAGCAAGGAUGUUCAAAAUCUUACAUAUAAUAAGUAAAAAGUAAGACUGAAUGUCUACGUUCGAAACAAAGUAAUAUGAAAAUAUUUAAACAGCAUUACAAAAUCCUAGUUUAUACUAGACUACCAUUUAAAAAUCAUGUUUUUAUAUAAAUGCCCAAAUUUGAGAUGCAUUAUUCCUAUUACUAAUGAUGUAAGUACGAGGAUAAAUCCAAGAAACUUUCAACUCUUUGCCUUUCCUGGCCUUUACUGGAUCCCAAAAGCAUUUAAGGUACAUGUUCCAAAAACUUUGAAAAGCUAAAUGUUUCCCAUGAUCGCUCAUUCUUCUUUUAUGAUUCAUACGUUAUUCCUUAUAAAGUAAGAACUUUGUUUUCCUCCUAUCAAGGCAGCUAUUUUAUUAAAUUUUUCACUUAGUCUGAGAAAUAGCAGAUAGUCUCAUAUUUAGGAAAACUUUCCAAAUAAAAUAAAUGUUAUUCUCUGAUAAAGAGCUAAUACAGAAAUGUUCAAGUUAUUUUACUUUCUGGUAAUGUCUUCAGUAAAAUAUUUUCUUUAUCUAAAUAUUAACAUUCUAAGUCUACCAAAAAAAGUUUUAAACUCAAGCAGGCCAAAACCAAUAUGCUUAUAAGAAAUAAUGAAAAGUUCAUCCAUUUCUGAUAAAGUUCUCUAUGGCAAAGUCUUUCAAAUACGAGAUAACUGCAAAAUAUUUUCCUUUUAUACUACAGAAAUGAGAAUCUCAUCAAUAAAUUAGUUCAAGCAUAAGAUGAAAACAGAAUAUUCUGUGGUGCCAGUGCACACUACCUUCCCACCCAUACACAUCCAUGUUCACUGUAACAAACUGAAUAUUCACAAUAAAGCUUCUGAGUAACACUUUCUGAUUACUCAUGAUAAACUGACAUGGCUAACUGCAAGAAUUAAAUCUUCUAUCUGAGAGUAAUAAUUUAUGAUGACUCAGUGGUGCCAGAGUAAAGUUUCUAAAAUAACAUUCCUCUCACUUGUACCCCACUAAAAGUAUUAGACUACACAUUACAUUGAAGUUAAACACAAAAUUAUCAGUGUUUUAGAAACAUGAGUCCGGACUGUGUAAGUAAAAGUACAAACAUUAUUUCCACCAUAAAGUAUGUAUUGAAAUCAAGUUGUCUCUGUGUACAGAAUACAUACUUAUUCCCAUUUUUAAGCAUUUGCUUCUGUUUUCCCUACCUAGAAUGUCAGAUGUUUUUCAGUUAUCUCCCCAUUUGUCAAAGUUGACCUCAAGAUAACAUUUUUCAUUAAAGCAUCUGAGAUCUAAGAACACAAUUAUUAUUCUAACAAUGAUUAUUAGCUCAUUCACUUAUUUUGAUAACUAAUGAUCACAGCUAUUAUACUACUUUCUCGUUAUUUUGUGUGCAUGCCUCAUUUCCCUGACUUAAACCUCACUGAGAGCGCAAAAUGCAGCUUUAUACUUUUUACUUUCAAUUGCCUAGCACAAUAGUGAGUACAUUUGAAUUGAAUAUAUAAUAAAUAUUGCAAAAUAAAAUCCAUCUAAAUAGAAGGGUUCUGUUUUAUUUGGAAAAAUUGAAUCUUUAAACUAUCAUAAUCUUGAAUGACUGUCAUCUUUCUAGUUUUCAGAAAAAUAAUGUAUUCCUAUAUUAUUUUUAUGAUAAAACUUAUGGAGCAAAACACCAUCAAAUAACUCUCAAAUUAAGAAAAAAUUCAAAAGUCAGUAGUUUUAGAUAAGAUAAUGAUAAGGGAGAAAGAACAUUGGUAAAAGGUAUGAAUUCCAGAAUUAAAGAAAUAAUUUGGGGAUUUCUAGAUAAGAGGAUAUAUAUGAACAUGCAUACCUUACACCUUCAUAUACACAACCUUAAAUCACAAAUAAAACAAAAUAAACAAUACAAAUUAUACCACCAAGAUUCAGAAGAUAUCAGACGAAAUAAUUAGAGAAAGUAAAAAUAUGCUGUCUCCAUUAUAUUCAUAAUGUUUCAUUCUUGACACUAAUAAUUAGAGGCUUUAAAUUUUUAAAUGAUUUACUUUUUACUAACAUUGCUGAAAAAAACUAAAGACAUACAUAAAUGGAAAGAUGUCUUGUGUUUAUGGAUGGUAAGAUUUAAUGUUGUUAAGACAACAAUACUAUCCAAUAUGAUAUGCAGACUGAACACAGUUGCCAUCAAAAUCUCAAUGAUGCUUUCACACAAAUAAAAUGGAACUUCAAGAGACCCCCAAAUAAAGAGAAGAAUCUUGAAAAUAAGAA